AGCGGCCGCCUUGCUCCUCUAGGUCCCAGGCGCUCUGCGGAGCUUUCGCUGCCCGGUGAGCGGCGCCGGGCUUGAGGUCGCCCAGACGUCGGAGGAGCCGGGUCACGAGGCUGGAGCUUCCUGCUUGCAGAGUGCGGCGGGGAGGCGCGGCCCGGGAACGCGGGAUCCUGGGGAGAUCUGCCUUCUGGAGACUGCGCCGUCCUCCCGGGAGAGCCAGAAAGAGGACAUGGCUGCUGGGCAGCGGGAAGCGAGGCCCCAGGUGUCACUGACAUUCGAGGACGUGGCUGUGCUCUUUACCUGGGAUGAGUGGAGAAAGCUGGCUCCUUCUCAGAGAAACUUGUACCGGGAUGUGAUGCUGGAGAACUAUAGGAACCUGGUCUCACUGGGACUCUCAUUUACCAAACCAAAAGUCAUCUCCCUGUUGCAGCAAGGAGAAGAUCCCUGGGAGGUGGAGAAAGACAGUUCUGGUGUCUCCUCUCUAGGAUGUAAGAGCACACCUAAAAUGACAAAGUCAACUCAAACUCAGGAUUCAUUUCAGGAGCAGAUAAGGAAAAGAUUGAAAAGGGAUGAACCCUGGAACUUCAUAUCAGAAAGAUCCUGCAUAUAUGAAGAGAAAUUAAAGAAACAGCAGGACAAAAAUGAAAAUUUACAAAUAAUUUCAGUUGCCCAUACAAAAAUCCUUACUGUAGAUAGAAGCCAUAAAAAUGUUGAAUUUGGCCAAAACUUCUACCUGAAAUCAGUCUUCAUUAAGCAACAGAGAUUUGCUAAAGAAAAAACUCCAUCAAAAUGUGAAAUACAAAGAAAUAGUUUCAAGCAGAAUUCAAAUUUACUUAACCAAUCAAAAAUCAAAACAGCAGAGAAACGCUAUAAAUGCAGUACAUGUGAAAAAGCCUUCAUUCACAAUUCAUCCCUUCGUAAACAUCAGAAAAACCACACUGGAGAAAAAUUAUUUAAAUGUAAAGAAUGUUUAAAAGCUUUCAGCCAAAGUUCUGCUCUUAUUCAACAUCAAAGAACUCAUACAGGAGAGAAACCCUAUAUAUGUAAAGAAUGUGGGAAAGCCUUCAGCCAUAGUGCAUCCCUUUGUAAGCAUUUAAGGACCCAUACUGUGGAGAAAUGCUAUAGAUGUAAAGAAUGUGGUAAAUCCUUCAGUCGAAGGUCUGGGCUUUUUAUACAUCAAAAAAUCCAUGCUCAAGAAAAUCCCCAUAAAUACAAUCCAGGCAGGAAGGCAUCCAGUUACAGCACUUCCCUUUCUGGAAGUCAGAAAAUUCAUCUCAGAAAGAAGUCCUACUUAUGUAAUGAAUGUGGCAACACCUUUAAGUCUAGCUCAUCCCUUCGUUAUCAUCAGAGAAUUCACACUGGAGAGAAGCCUUUUAAAUGUAGUGAAUGUGGGAGAGCCUUCAGCCAGAGUGCCUCUCUUAUUCAACAUGAAAGAAUUCACACCGGAGAAAAGCCCUAUAGAUGCAAUGAAUGUGGGAAAGGCUUUACUUCUAUUUCACGACUUAAUAGACACCGAAUAAUUCAUACUGGAGAGAAAUUGUAUAAUUGUAAUGAAUGUGGUAAAGCCUUAAGCUCCCACUCAACACUUAUUAUUCAUGAGCGAAUUCAUACUGGAGAAAAACCAUGUAAAUGUAAAGUAUGUGGAAAAGCCUUCAGACAGAGUUCCGCUCUCAUUCAACAUCAGAGAAUGCAUACUGGAGAAAGACCCUAUAAGUGUAACGAAUGUGACAAAACAUUCAGGUGUAACUCAUCGCUUAGUAAUCACCAGAGAAUUCAUACUGGAGAGAAACCAUAUCGAUGUUUAGAAUGUGGGAUGUCUUUUGGCCAAAGUGCAGCUCUUAUACAACAUCAGAGGAUUCAUACAGGAGAAAAACCCUUUAAAUGUAAUACAUGUGGAAAAACUUUUAGACAAAGCUCAUCACUUAUUGCACAUCAAAGAAUUCAUACUGGAGAGAAACCCUAUGAAUGUAAUGCAUGUGGGAAACUCUUUAGCCAGAGGUCAUCCCUUACUAAUCAUUAUAAAAUUCACAUUGAAGAGGACUCCUUAAAAGCCGAUUUGCAUGUGUGAAAGCCUUAAACCAAAACUCAUCAGAGAAUACAUGCUUGAGAGUGAUUUAUUAAAUAUAAUGAAUAUGAGAAAACUCUUAGUUCUCAUCAGAUACUAAGUUUUAAGAAUAAACUUUAGCUAUGUAAUAACUUAUGGGAAAAGCUUUUAUACUUGUCACUCACUUUUUAAAAUAUCCCGAGACAGUUCACUGUUGCAGACAUUGAAAUUGGCCAUUUGUAAGAUAAAAGGUAUGUUUAUAAAAUCUCUUUAUAUAAUAUAUGCUAUCUAUGACAUGCAAAAAAGAAAAGUCUGGGUGCUGAGGUGCUGAAUUUUUCAUUAGAAAAACAUUUGUAUAAACUACUAUUAUAUAAAUAUAAGCAUAUUUAUUACAGCAAACAUUUUAAUAGCAAACAAAACAAUUGAUCUUAAAAAUAUAUGCAAUAUAUACUUACCUGGCAGGGAAGAUUACCAUGAUCACGAAGGUGGUUUUCCCAGGGCAAGGCUUAUCCAUUGCACUCCAGAUGUGCUGACCCCUUCAAUUUCCCAAAAUGUGGAAAACUCAACUGCAUAAUUUAUGGUAGUGGGGGACUACAUUCGCACUUUCUCCUGAAAUAUAUAUAUAUAUGCAGUAUUAGAGCAAAGGACCAAUAAGAGAUAAAAACUAACUGAACUACCUCUUAGUGCCUGGAAUUUACCUUUUCCUGACUUACUGUCAAACUUCGUGCAUGGCUUUUAUUAAAAAAGAAAAAA